AAGAGGAGGCGCGAGAAUGGAGGUGGAGGCCGUCUGUGGUGGCGCGGGCGAGGUGGAGGCCCAGGACUCUGACCCUGCCCCUGCCUUCAGCAAGGCCCCCGGCAGCGCCGGCCACUACGAACUGCCGUGGGUUGAAAAAUAUAGGCCAGUAAAGCUGAAUGAAAUUGUCGGGAAUGAAGACACCGUGAGCAGGCUAGAGGUCUUUGCAAGGGAAGGAAAUGUGCCCAACAUCAUCAUUGCGGGGUCAGAGGUGACGGAGAUGCAAACAGCAGUGAACAUAACUCAAGAGCUACCUGAGGUCCUUCUGGUGGUUUGAAGUCUUUACUGGAGAUCUCAUUCCCAGGGCCCUCCAGGAACCGGCAAGACCACAAGCAUUCUGUGCUUGGCCCGGGCCCUGCUGGGCCCAGCACUCAAAGAUGCCAUGUUGGAACUCAAUGCUUCAAAUGACAGGGGCAUUGACGUUGUGAGGAAUAAAAUUAAAAUGUUUGCUCAACAAAAAGUCACUCUUCCCAAAGGCCGACAUAAGAUCAUCAUUCUGGAUGAAGCAGACAGCAUGACCGACGGAGCCCAGCAAGCCUUGAGGAGAACCAUGGAAAUCUACUCUAAAACCACUCGCUUCGCCCUUGCUUGUAAUGCUUCGGAUAAGAUCAUCGAGCCCAUUCAGUCCCGCUGUGCAGUCCUCCGGUACACAAAGCUGACCGACGCCCAGAUCCUCACCAGGCUGAUGAAUGUUAUCGAGAAGGAGAGGGUACCCUACACUGAUGACGGCCUAGAAGCCAUCAUCUUCACGGCCCAGGGAGACAUGAGGCAGGCGCUGAACAACCUGCAGUCCACCUUCUCAGGAUUUGGCUUCAUUAACAGUGAGAACGUGUUCAAGGUCUGUGACGAGCCCCACCCACUGCUGGUAAAGGAGAUGAUCCAGCACUGUGUGAAUGCCAACAUUGACGAAGCCUACAAGAUUCUUGCUCACUUGUGGCAUCUGGGCUACUCACCAGAAGAUAUCAUUGGCAACAUCUUUCGAGUGUGUAAAACUUUCCAAAUGGCAGAAUACCUGAAACUGGAGUUUAUCAAGGAAAUUGGAUACACUCACAUGAAAAUAGCGGAAGGAGUGAACUCUCUUUUGCAGAUGGCAGGCCUCCUGGCAAGGCUGUGUCAGAAGACAAUGGCCCCGGUGGCCAGUUAGAGCAGAGACUUCACUGACUGACUUACAGGUGCCCUAUUCUGAGGUACAGGAGCCGCGGCUUUCUGAUGGGGGAAAAUGCCGCCUUAGGCUGGAGCCAACAUGACUGUCCUUUAAACUCCAGUGGCUGGCCAGGCACGGUAGCUCACGCCUGUAAUCCCAACACUUUGGGAGGCCGAGGCAGGUGGAUCACCUGAGGUCAGAAGUUCAAGACCAGCCUGGCCAACAUGGGGAAACCCUGUCUUUACUAAAAAUAUAAAAAUUAGCUGGGUGUGGUGGCGGGCACCUGUAAUCCCAGCUACUCGGGAGGCUGUGGCAGGAGAAUCGCUUGAACCCAGGAGGUGGAGGUUGCAGUGAGCCAAGAUCACACCAUUGCACUCCAGCCUGGGCGACAGAGUCUCCAUCUGGGGAAAAAAAUUAAAUAAAUAAACUCCCGUGACUUGCAUGUUUGCUUCUGGGACGUCUGUGCCCCGCAAGUGUUUGAGUUUGGCCUCCACCCCAUUGAUGCGGUGACGGGGCGGAAAGGCGCAGAGAAGCUGAGGGCGGUCUCUGAUCUGUGUGUGGGUUGACAUUUUAGCUAAUAAAGCCUUGCAGUGUUUGUUGGCAA